GAAGGCGUGAGGGCGGGCAGCAGCGACAGGAUGCUUGUUUUUCGCUCUACCAAAGUCGUCUGAAGGCGAGACAGCGGGCCCAGGGCGCAGGACCCACCGCAGCCCCCUGGGCAGUCUCCUCGCCCCGCGUCCGCGUCGUCUCCGGGGCACUUAGUAAGGGGUGGGGAGAGCUUGCCCUCCCUCUUAAGCUGAGGAGAAACACCCGAAGACACCGCAGGAGCCUGUGAAAGUCCCUAGGACUCCAAGUGAGGAAGUGACACUCCCAGGCGAGCCGGCCCGCGGCUGCCAGUCUGCACGGCCUCGGCACGGCGGCCCCGGAGCGGCGCGGGGUGGAUCUCAGGCUCUGCCGGCCCGCGGCCCGCGGGGUCCAUGCGCAGGGCCCCCAGCCCAAGUUCUUCCAUCUUCCGAUGCGGCCCCCCAGAGCCGCGGGGCAGCCGGUGAUCUAGCCCGGGAGCCCAUCUUACAGCGGUGCCAAGCAGAGGGGCGGCAGAGACGGAGGGGCAGCCUCUUUGGGACUAACUCAUGAAGAACAAGGGUGCUAAGCAGAAGCUGAAACGAAAGGGAGCCGCCAGCGCGUUUGGCUGUGACCUGACGGAGUAUCUGGAAAGCUCGGGACAGGAUGUUCCAUACGUUUUGAAGAGCUGUGCAGAAUUUAUAGAGACUCACGGCAUCGUGGAUGGAAUCUAUCGGCUUUCAGGAGUCACCUCAAACAUACAACGGCUAAGGCAAGAGUUUGGCUCAGAUCAAUGUCCAGAUCUGACAAGGGAAGUGUACCUCCAGGACAUCCACUGUGUGGGCUCGCUUUGCAAGCUCUACUUUAGGGAGCUGCCCAACCCCCUCCUGACUUAUGAGCUCUAUGAGAAAUUCACGGAGGCAGUGUCGCAUUGCCCUGAAGAAGGCCAACUGGCCCGAAUCCAAAAUGUUAUCCAGGAGCUUCCUCCAUCCCACUAUAGGACCUUGGAAUACCUGAUUCGACACCUGGCCCAUAUCGCCUCCUUCAGCAGCAAGACCAACAUGCACGCCCGGAACCUGGCCCUGGUGUGGGCGCCAAACCUCCUCAGGUCUAAAGAAAUUGAAGCCACUGGUUGCAAUGGAGAUGCAGCCUUCCUUGCAGUCCGGGUCCAGCAGGUGGUGAUUGAGUUCAUAUUGAAUCAUGUAGAUCAAAUCUUUAACAACGGUGCACCUGGGUCUCUGGAGAAUGAUGAAAACCGGCCCAUCAUGAAGAGCCUGACCUUGCCAGCCCUCUCCCUGCCCAUGAAGCUGGUGAGCCUUGAGGAAGCUCAAGCCCGCAGCCUGGCCACUAACCAUCCUGCUCGCAAGGAAAGGAGGGAGAACAGCCUGCCUGAGAUUGUCCCUCCCAUGGGCACCCUCUUCCACACUGUCCUUGAGUUACCAGACAACAAGCGAAAGCUCUCCAGUAAAUCAAAGAAGUGGAAAUCAAUAUUUAACCUGGGACGUUCUGGAUCAGACUCCAAAUCAAAACUGAGUAGAAAUGGGAGUGUAUUUGUGAGAGGACAGAGGCUCUCGGUGGAAAAGGCUACUAUCCGACCAGCUAAAAGCAUGGACUCACUAUGUUCAGUGCCUGUGGAAGGAAAAGAAACCAAGGGAAAUUUCAAUCGAACAGUUACCACCGGUGGAUUUUUCAUUCCAGCAACAAAGAUGCACUCCACCGGCACCGGCAGCUCAUGUGACCUCACCAAGCAGGAGGGCGAAUGGGGCCAGGAGGGGAUGCCUCCCGGGGCUGAGGGUGGCUUUGAUGUGAGCAGUGAUCGCAGCCAUCUCCAGGGCGCUCAGGCCCGGCCCCCACCGGAACAGCUGAAGGUUUUCCGGCCUGUUGAGGAUCCGGAGAGCGAGCAAACAGCCCCAAAGAUGUUGGGUAUGUUCUACACUUCGAACGACAGCCCUAGCAAAUCCGUCUUCACCAGCAGCCUCUUCCAGAUGGAGCCCUCGCCGCGUAACCAGCGCAAGGCGCUGAACAUCUCCGAGCCCUUUGCGGUAUCUGUGCCGCUCCGCGUGUCCGCAGUCAUCAGCACCAACAGCACGCCGUGCAGAACACCCCCGAAGGAGCUGCAGUCUCUUUCCAGCCUGGAAGAGUUUUCUUUUCAUGGAUCAGAGAGCGGAGGCUGGCCAGAAGAAGAGAAACCGCUGGGAGCUGAGACUUCUGCAGCUUCUGUACCUAAGAAGGCAGGUCUUGAGGAUGCCAAGGCAGUACCUGAAGCACCGGGGACAGUGGAAUGCAGCAAAGGCCUGUCCCAGGAGCCAGGCGCCCACCUGGAGGAGAAGAAAACCCCAGAAAGCUCCUUGAGCUCUCAACAUUUAAAUGAAUUAGAGAAGAGGCCAAAUCCGGAGAAGGUGGUGGAGGAGGGACGAGAGGCUGGUGAGAUGGAGUCCAGCACCCUGCAGGAGAGCCCCAGGGCCAGAGCCGAAGCUGUGCUUCUCCAUGAGAUGGAUGAAGAUGAUCUGGCCAAUGCCCUGAUCUGGCCUGAGAUUCAACAGGAGCUGAAAAUCAUUGAAUCUGAGGAGGAGCUCUCAUCGUUGCCACCUCCUGCUCUGAAGACCAGCCCAAUUCAGCCUAUUCUCGAGUCGAGUCUGGGGCCCUUUAUUCCCUCAGAGCCUCCUGGGAGCUUGCCUUGUGGCUCCUUCCCUGCUCCAGUCUCCACCCCUCUGGAGGUGUGGACUAGGGAUCCAGCCAAUCAGAGCACACAGGGGGCUUCCACAGCAGCCAGCAGAGAGAAGCCGGAACCUGAGCAGGGCCUGCACCCAGACCUCGCCAGCCUGGCUCCUCUGGAAAUAGUUCCUUUUGAGAAGGCAUCUCCACAAGCAACAGUGGAAGUAGGAGGCCCAGGCAAUCUGUCUCCUCCACUCCCACCUGCUCCUCCCCCUCCAACUCCUCUGGAGGAGUCAACUCCAGUCCUGCUUUCAAAGGGCGGCCCGGAAAGAGAAGACUCAUCCAGGAAAUUGAGGACAGAUCUCUACAUAGACCAGCUGAAGUCCCAAGACAGCCCUGAGAUCUCUAGCCUCUGUCAGGGAGAGGAGGCAACCCCAAGACACAGUGACAAGCAAAAUUCAAAGAAUGCUGCUUCUGAGGGGAAAGGCUGUGGUUUUCCAAGCCCAACCAGGGAGGUUGAGAUCGUCUCACAAGAAGAGGAGGAUGUAACCCAUUCAGUACAGGAGCCUUCAGACUGUGACGAAGAUGACACUGUGACAGACAUUGCCCAGCAUGGCCUGGAGAUGGUGGAGCCCUGGGAGGAACCCCAGUGGGUGACGAGUCCCCUUCACUCUCCCACCCUGAAAGACGCGCACAAGGCCCAGGUACAGGGCCUUCAGGGUCACCAGUUGGAGAAGAGGCUUUCCCACAGGCCCAGCCUUCGCCAGAGCCAUUCUCUAGAUAGCAAACCCACGGUUAAAAGCCAGUGGACUCUCGAGGUUCCCUCCUCCAGCAGCUGUGCUAAUCUUGAAACAGAGAGGAAUUCUGACCCUCUUCAGCCCCAGGCACCCAGGAGAGAGAUUACUGGAUGGGAUGAGAAAGCCCUGAGGUCCUUCAGAGAGUUCUCUGGCCUGAAAGGGGCAGAGGCUCCUCCCAACCAGAAGGGACCAAGUGGUGUGCAACCCAACCCAGCAGAAACCAGCCCCAUCAGCCUAGCAGAGGGAAAGGAGCUAGGGACACACCUGGGGCACAGCAGUCCACAGAUUAGGCAAGGUGGUGUUCCUGGGCCAGAGAGCAGCAAGGAGAGUUCACCCAGCGUGCAGGACAGCACUUCGCCUGGAGAGCACCCCGCAAAGUUACAGCUAAAGAGCACAGAGUGUGGGCCCCCAAAAGGGAAAAACAGGCCUUCUUCCCUCAACUUGGACCCUGCCAUUCCCAUUGCUGACCUCUUCUGGUUUGAGAAUGUGGCCUCAUUUAGUUCACCUGGAAUGCAGGUCUCUGAGCCAGGAGACCCAAAGGUCACAUGGAUGACCUCAUCUUACUGUAAAGCAGACCCCUGGAGGGUUUACUCCCAGGACCCCCAGGACCUGGACAUUGUUGCUCAUGCACUGACAGGCCGCCGUAACUCAGCUCCUGUGAGUGUGUCAGCUGUGAGAACCUCCUUCAUGGUCAAAAUGUGCCAGGCCAGGGCGGUCCCAGUCAUCCCUCCCAAGAUUCAGUACACCCAGAUCCCACAGCCCCUGCCCUCUCAGAGCUCAGGGGAGAAUGGGGUUCAGCCUCUGGAGAGGAGCCAGGAGGGACCCAGCUCAACCAGUGGGACCACUCAGAAACCUGCCAAAGAUGAUUCUCCCUCCUCCCUGGAAAGCUCAAAGGAAGAAAAACCAAAGCAAGAUCCCGGAGCCAUUAAGUCCUCACCAGUGGAUGCCACUGCACCCUGCAUGUGCGAGGGACCUACCCUUUCUCCAGAACCAGGCUCGUCUAACCUGCUCUCCACCCAGGAUGCAGUAGUGCAAUGCAGAAAGCGCAUGUCAGAGACAGAGCCAUCUGGGGACAACCUUCUUUCUUCAAAACUAGAGCGACCAUCUGGGGGUUCUAAGCCUUUCCACAGGUCAAGGCCAGGAAGACCUCAGAGCCUAAUCUUAUUCAGUCCUCCUUUCCCCAUUAUGGACCACCUGCCCCCUUCAUCCACAGUGACAGAUUCCAAGGUCCUGCUGUCCCCUAUCAGAAGUCCCACCCAGACAGUUUCCCCUGGCCUUCUUUGUGGAGAGUUGGCAGAAAACACAUGGGUCACACCAGAAGGGGUUACACUUAGGAAUAAAAUGACCAUCCCUAAGAAUGGCCAGAGACUAGAGACCUCAACCAGCUGUUUUUACCAGCCUCAGCGGAGAUCAGUAAUUCUGGAUGGAAGAAGUGGGAGGCAAAUAGAAUGAUUUCGGUUCACCUGCUGGUGUCUGAAAAAAACCGUGAUUCAUCUGGAAGUUAUUACAGGGCCAGCUUGCCAUAUUCCAGGCACACGUUAUCAAGUUUGGGCCUAUUGUGGCCUCUGACUUCUCUUUCUUCAGCCUUUUGACCACUUAUUAAUUAGUCCAUUUGCUAGAAGAGUGGUCAAGGGAAAAACGAGAGAUGAAAUUUAGUUAAGUCUAUGUGAGCAAGUGAGAGAAGGUUAGGUAAGGGGAGAGGAUGGAAUGCUUGCCUCCAAUGAACUUUGGAGCUUGUAUGUGAGUCAGAUUGCUCCCCUAUUGCUAUUAUCUAUUACUCUUGAGAGCUGGCUGUCCUUUGAAAGAAAGAAGUAAUGUUCUUUGAAAGAAAGAAAAAUCUCUUGCUGUGUCAAACCUCAAAAUGUUGCUAUUGGGGUUAGAAGGCCUCCUCUUUAUGCUUUUUAAUGCUCUUUCAAACGUGUUCUUUUAGACCAGUUUUCUAAUAAGCUUUGUAAAAUGUACUAUCCAAAUUAGAAGCGGAUUUGGAAAUGCAAACUAACGUGCACUUAGAUAUCCAAGUGGGUGAGCUUAGCCACUCUUACCCAUGCUCUUUCCCUGGAAUCCCUGGAGACCUGUCCAAGAUGAUUUCCAUAUACCAGCAUAGAAAAUCAGAAUCAAGAGCAAACUCUGAGACUGGCACAAUCCAAGAAGAUUUCCUGGCUCUGGCUUUUAGUAAUUUGGGACUCCAACUGCCACUGUACUGGACUGUAAUUUAUAAAUCCAGUAGCUACGCAGGGUGGAGGCUGGGCUGAGGAUUACCAUAAUGAAAUGUACUAAAUCUUCAUUUAGGUAUGCAAUUGUGAAGUGAAGGCAUCUGCUUUCUUUACAGUAUCAGAGUCCAAGAACAGGAUGUCACCAUAGAUAAAAGCCUCAUACAAAGGCAGAACUACACUCCAAAUUUAAUGUGUUUAAAUUGGUGGGGCACCAGCAGAAAAUAUUCUAGCUCAGCUUUACUCUUCUUCCACACUAGGCUGGGCCCAGCAAUACAGGAGAGGAUGAAGGGAGGAGCUCCAGGAGGCGAGGGAAGAGCCCUAGCAGGGCGGCCAUCACAACCACUCACUGAGAGUUGCCCUUCUUAAAAAUGUAUUUUAUUUUAGCCAGUGGGUCCCUUCCUUUCUCCUUUCCUCUCUACUGCUCAAGAACAGAUUUGAGGCCAGGUGCGGUGCCUCACAUCUGUAAUCCCAACACUUUGGGAGGCUGAGAUGGGUGGAUUGCUUGAGCCCAGGAGUUCAAGACCAGCCUGGGCAACACAGCGAGACCCCAUCUCUUAAAAAAUAACAGACUUGAGGAACCCCUCUCCCUUCCAUAAUUCCCCUCAUCCACCGCCCACUCCAGGCACUCACUCAAACUUGCUCUUCAACUCUGUAUACAAGCAGAAGCAAUAAACCAAUCUGAUUUUCUUUUCAAUUAUUUAUAACUUUCAAUGGUUCUUUCCUUUCCAGCUGGCGAGAGAAAGGAGAACUAAUAUACCUGCUGGCAGAUUUUUGGUGCUGCCCAAAAAAGGACUUCACAGGGCAUCUCUUCUCAGGUUCAAGCCUGGCUGAAUUCUGCCCAGAAGCUCAGUCAUUGCAGAAAUUUCUCUAAGGGCUGAUAGUACCUCUGGGUAGGCGUCACAACCAAGGCUGGUUCUGGGCUUAGUGGGGGCUGAGAUGAAGUUACCUCCUCCAAUGAGAAAUUGGGAGCUGAUGCCCUGCAACAGAUAUAUAUUCCUCUCUCUCUCUGUCUCUCUAUCUCUCUCCUCCCUCUCCCUCCCUCCCUCCCCGCCAAUAAGCCUUACAAACAGUUUUGAAAUCUUGUUCUGUACCUUUUAAGCCAGUGUCUGUGGCGAGGGUGACUGGCAAGUCAGCUGAUGAGUUCUGCCUUCUGAGAGCACUGAGUGAGCAAGGCCUUUCAUCAGUGUUUUGGCCUUCUCAUUGGGUGAGGAAGACAUUGAACCAACAGCCAACGAGAUAUGAACCUGUAAGAAAAAAGUCCUAGAAUAUAGUAUUUUUCCCCAGGCCAGCAAAGUGAAGAAAUACAGUGGUGACAGAUGAGAAAGGCCAUGUUCAAGAGAUCUGAAAAGUACAUUCCUGCCUUAUCAGAAAAUGUGUCAGACAGGUUUUAUGUCAGCCUCAGUGCUCCUGCGGUGUCGACGCUCUGAUAAGGACCAUGUUCCAGUUAGAAUGCGAGGGAGGGAAAGAGCUGCACUUUGCUUCACCAUCAGAACUCUGAGCCAAAUAAUGAAUAUGUAAACUAUUUUAUGAUUAUUUUAAAUGUUUGUUUGGUAACAUUUAUAAGAUCUAUUUUUAUUUGGGGAUAGACUGAGAAGCCACCAUUUACAUAUUAACAAGUGACUUCAGUUCUAAGGGUUGAGAUGCCUGUGUGGAUUUAUAAAAUGGUUGCAAGAUCUUUUAGACUCUGACAUUUAUAGCAUCACCUUCAGGAACACAGUUCUGGGGAUGUCAUCAUGAGACACACUGACAGCUGUGGAGAUAGUCCCUACUCUCAGCUUUCCUUGCUAGUCAAGUCCAAAAGGCCUUAGAAGCUGACUCACCUUCUCAGCCAGAGUCCUGCUGCUCAAGUGUGGACCUCCACUUUGACUCUCACCCAGCCUGCCAGCCAUCACAAAGGCUUUCAUAAACUUCCUGUGGUCUGGGCUAGCCUGGCACUGAUGAAAUUCCAUUCUAAAGAAAGAAAACUCAUAUUCCUCCCCCCCACAAAUUGUUCCCCCAAAUGCUCUGGGAUUACCUAUUUCACCACUCAUUUGAGUCUCCGAAAAAUGAACUCCCUGAGAAUGGCUGGAUGGGAAUCAGAUAGUCUGCUUCCAUUCAGGAGAGGGACAGAACAGGAGCUGCUGUGUUUAGGAGGAUUUACCUGGUGCCCUAGAAAGGGCUAUGCAAUCAAAUUCUCAAGGGCUCCUUCAAAUCAGCUAUCAGUCCUCAAAAUGGGGGUUGCUGAUGUUAAAUGAUGGAUUUGCAGUGAAACGCAUGCAUGUACUGACGUUUUCUUUCAGCAUUAGUGGUUGCUUAAGAAAAUAGUAACCUAUAUUUUCUGCUACACUUGGAAUAUGAAGAAAUCUGAACAAGAACCCCAUUAAGACACCUAACCUAAUCUAAACCCUAAAAUUCAAAAUAUUGUCCAAGUCAAAAGUCUAGACUCUGAGGACAUUAAAAAUGUAAAUAUCAUCAUCCUUAGCAAAUAUUUAUUGGGAGCUUAGUAAUAGUGCACUGGGUACCUUAGCACUCCCAAAUCAUUCAAGAGUCUAGUGAAAAAGGGGGAGGGAUGGCAGCAAAUAAAACACCCCCAUAAACAACCAGGAGCAAGGUUGAGAACCAUUAAGUUGCCAAACAAAAGCAGAAGGGGAAAAAGUGUGGCAACAAGCAUCUUUUAAUAGGAUAGUUGACGGUAUUCAAGUGACCUACUGACUCCAAAUAAUCAAAUUGAACACAAUUGCAAAUCCAAUAGAACAUCCCAGUGAGACACUCGGGUAUUUGAGAACUUUGCUUGAUUUAGAAAACUGGAAAGUGGCAACUAGGCUAGAAUAGUGGCAACUAGGUUCGGAGGUUUCGUGUGGUCAUAAUUGGUUUGGUGAAGUGUGAGAUCUCUGCAAAUGAGCCAGGUAAGAUCAGUAUUCCAUAGUGCUUGAAAAGGGGAUUUUAGAGACUUCUGUCAUCACAAAGCAGAUUAACUCCUAGUUAAUGAUGAAGCAGUAGGCCCAAGAUAAACUGUUCAAUUCAAGAUAAAUUGUUCUUGUCAGUGUUUGGCAUAUGAUAAUCACAUUUGGCUAAAAUUGGAUGGGACAGUCAUUUGUCUACACAGGCCUUCCAUUCCUGCAUGAAGAGAUACUGGGGAGCAUACAAUUAUUUUGUCCAGUAUUAGAGUGGGAGAAGUUCUCAGUAAGUCCAGUCCCACCAGGAUUUAUUUGGGCCACAUUCUACCACGGCCAGUCCAAUCUGAUGACCACAUGAAUUGGGGUUAAGUGUUGCUAAGACUAUGAUUUUAGACAUGUCUGGCAGGAAGGUCAGCUCAAAAUGUGGCAUGACAAAGAAUAUGUGCUCUACUACCAAAACCUUUCCUAGCAAAACAAGGCCAGAAGAGGGAGCAAGCAUCUUUCCAAGCAUGGAGAGGAGGGGGCAAUGGUGGAAGGGUGAUUGCCUGAAAUCAGUGCCAGUACAGAUAGCAUAAAAUUGGGGGCCACCACAGAUUGGCUGGCUACUGUGUAGAUCAUUUAGUAAUCUUGAGGUACAUUAAUAAUGCAGAGAUUACUUUUCUGUGAGGGUAAGGGGGACGUAGCUAAAUAUAAGAAGCUUACAAGGUCCAUAGCCAUGUAUUUUACUGGAUAAAUCACAAUGCUUUGCAAUAACUUAAUGUCAUAGUACUUUCUGGCUUAUAAUUCUGCAAAGUAAAGCACUUUUUCAAAGGA